GUCGUGUUCUGGAAGCUUAGCGGUCACCAUGGAGCUGCUGGGAGAGUACGUCGGGCAGGAAGGGAAGCCGCAGAAGCUGCGGGUGUCCUGUGAGGCGCCGGGUGACGGCGACCCUUUCCAGGGCCUGUUGUCUGGCGUGGCCCAGAUGAAGGACAUGGUAACGGAAUUAUUCGACCCUCUGGUACAGGGGGAAGUGCAGCACCGGGUGGCGGCGGCUCCAGACGAGGACUUGGACGGUGAUGAUGAAGAUGAUGCAGAAGAUGAAAAUAACAUUGAUAACAGAACUAACUUCGAUGGACCAUCUGCAAAACGGCCAAAAACACCGUCUUAACAAUAGCCUUCAUGACAUUUAAAAGAUGGCUGUUGUAUCCUUAUUGUCACACUAGGACAUUUAAGGAAGACUUAUGCUCUAAUUUGGAAAAAGCAUUUGUGUUGUUCUCCUGGGACAAUUUUGUCAAAGAGAAAACUGGUUUUUCUGUUUCUAGCAAAGAUAGUAAAGGCUUAGAAAUAAAAUCUGUUUUCUUGAGAAAUAAAUUUCAGACCCUGGAAGGAAAAUAGAACACUUCAUAAUGUAUAAAAUCCUCUAAGUUGGCAACUGAAUUUUUAUCAUUGUUUUCUAUUUUUAAAAUAAUCAUUGAUUUGUGUGAUGUCUACAUCUUUUAACUUCUGGUUCUGUUAUAAAGAGUACAUGUCACGGUUCAUAGGCAGUAACAUUUCAGAGAACUGACAUGAACAAGUAGUGAAAAUUGGGCAUUAAAUAUAAAAAUAACAGUUCUUCAUAAACAGAAGGAAAAUAAGGAAAUAGAAAUACCGACGAGAAAGGAGAGUCCUUGAAAGAGACCCAAGGAAACCCUGAAUUCAUACCCACGUCAAAUAUGCACAUAUCCUGAGAUGAUGCCACUUUGAUGAAUGUGCAUUAGUCUGAUUUAUCAUGUACCUUAAGAGAGCCAGAUGGGGUAUGUUUUUGUGCUGUGAUAUGGUAUUUAUACAGGUACAAAUAUAAGGCCUUAAGUAAACAAUCUGCAUUGAUUACAAUUUGGAUAUUUCCUCUCCUCCUGUAGCCAUACUUUGAUUUUGCUUUAAAAAGAUUAUUGAAUCCUUUUAAAAAUAUAUAUUCCUAAAAUA